GCCAUUUGACUUUGCUUCUUAGUGUGUGCAGUGGUGAAGAUGCUGUAUGAUUUCCUUGGUCAUAAAUAGCCUUAGUGGUAUCUAUGGAUUCCUUAGUGUGUUAGGGUGCAGUUAUUGGUUACUUUUUCAGGUUUCAGUGGUAGCAGUGGUGGGCCAAGUGUGUUUCUCCUUGAGACCUCAGGCAGCAUAUGCUGGCACCUGUACUGGCAGUUCCAGGCAAGUCGAUUCUUGGGCCUGUGGGGGGCUUUUUUGGAUGCUGAUUGUAGUAGUGGUGUACUGGGCAGGUGAGUGGGCUUUUGACCUUUUGGGCAGCGAGGAUGGUGGGGGCAGUGGGUAUAAAGGUGGUCAUGAAAUGUUCUUCUAGUUCUCAAGCACAGUGCUUUUGUGUUAGCCGUUGUUUCAAGUUUCAAUGGGCUGUGUGGGCCAGCCUCCAGGCUAGUAGAUGGUGCUUGCAGGUAACAACGAGCGGUGGGGGUAGCAUGGAGAUUUAUGCCCGACCUCUGUUCCCCAGAAGAGGUAUUUGGGUAACCCAGGUGGUAGUUGGGUUGUGGAACACCCAGGAGCCUGGAUCCCACACUCUGUCUUGGAGUAGGGGGCAAAGUUGGGCAGAGCUGGACCAAGCAAGCUUGUAUUCAGGCCCUCCAAUGGCAUAUGCAUGCACCAGCCUUGAUUAGGGGGUAGAGGAAGUCCUUAGGCCGCUUGUGAAAUGCUUGGUGAGGGGCAACCUUUGCUGUCCUGAAGUCUUAGGAUAGGGAGGAUAGGGCUGUCCCAGUGGCCACUGCUUUGGCCCACAGGAAUGAGACUUGCUUUCGUCUCACACCCCAGUCCCAGCAAAGUUCCCUCCUCCAUCCUGGCUAUGGCAGCCAACUUGGCCACCCAGUCAGUCCUGGCAGGCUGCACCUAGUCCACAACUCAGUCCUAGGCCAUAGGAGAUGCCAUUCAGCUUAAGGCCAAGCCUCCACAACAACUCUCCUCUUGCUUAGGACCUGGGAUGGUGGUGUGCCUGGUUGCAAUGCCAGUGGCUGGAGCCCACUCCACACUUGCUUCUCAGAACGGGCCGCAAGGGUUCAUCCCCCGCUCAAGCCCCAGUCCUGCAAGCACCACCCAAGUUCUCCCAUGCACAGCCUGUAAGAGCUCCGAUCCAGAAUGUUGUCCCACAGCAGCCAGCCAGGUUUCAAAAAGGGUGUAGGACAUUCCCUGGAGCAGUUCCAUAUCAUAGUCUUCUUGCCACUCCCCAGGUUAAGAUUCGUGGUGUGGGAGAGUCAAGGUGCUCUCCUACGGCCUGGAUUGUAUAAUUCCCCAGUGGGAAAGUGGACAGCAGAAAGGCACUCACUCACCCUCUCCCAUUUGGGGGAUUCGCUCCCCUUUCCCAGCUGGCCUCAGCCACACAGCUUUCCUGUUUUCUUUCUUCCUGGAUUUCAAAGCUUCCUCUCACUUUUUUGUUGAACUCCCAAGUUCUUUCUUGAACACUGCAUUUAAAGUGCAGUUGUCUGCACACUUGCUUGGUUUCUCUAAGCGGAUGAGAUUACUGGAAAUGCUUGUAGUCAGCCAUCUUGAAAAAAAAGAUCUUGUGUUUUAAGCAUCAUUGUGUGUUUGCCAACAGGAAGCAUACUGUAUGUAAAUAUUGAAUUGUUAUAUACCUUGGAUUUCUUUUCUCCUUUCAUUCUUUUAAGUUCUCUGCACCCUUAUGAGCAUGAUUUCCUAAUCCACAGCACAAUUUAGCCUGGAGGGGUGUGCAAUCAUUGUUAUUCCAUGUGUUCUGGUCUUUCUCACCAGCUACAUUUGAUAUUAAAAUAGAUGAUAUUUACUUAUUUCCAUGAAUUCCCUCAUCUCUCCUGCCCUCAGCUCCUAACAACAGACAGAUACUUAUUUAUUCAUUUGGUCAACAACUCUUUCUUUAAUAUGUGCUAUGUGCCCAGUUCUAUGCUAACACUGGGGCACAACAGUGAGAAAGAGAGAGAAAGAGGAGAGAGAAAAAAAAAAAGCCAAAGUCUUUUCUCUCAAAGAGCUCACAAGCUAGGAGAAGACACAGCAAUUACUUUUAAAGAGCCAAGGGAAAACAUAGUUACAACUGUGAAAAGAGCCAUGUGGGAAAAACACAUGACACUAUAUGAGGAAAAAAUAUCUUUGUCAAGUAGGUCAAGGAAGGCUUCCUUGAAAUAGUGAUGAUUAAGCUUAACUCUGGAAGGCCAGCAGAAGCUAACUAGACAGAAAAGGGGGAAGCAGAAUGGUGUCUUAGUCACAGGGAAUAGCAUGUGCAAAGGUCCUGUGACAGAAAGAAGAACAGGCUCUGGAGUGAGGGGAGGGUAAUAAAAGGGGAGAUAGCUUUGUUAAGGAUGUUGGUCUUCAUCCUAACAGCAAUAGGUAGUCAUUGGGGAUUUCAAGGAAAAAGGUGAAAAAAAUCAGAUUCUAUUUAAAAGAUCAUUCUACUUGCUGUGUGGAAAAUGGAUUGGGCUGGAGGUGGCAGAUCAGAAUGAAAGCAGGAGACCAGAUAUGAAACUCAAGCCAUUGUCCAGGCAGAAAGGACAGAUGGUGGGUUGGACACGGGUGGUGGCAGUGGAGAUGCAGAAAAGCAAACAGGUUUGCACAAUGUUUUGGAGGCAACAUUGCCAGGGGGUGGGAGUGAAUUUGAUAUGCAGAGAGAAUGUGGAGUCAGAUGAGUCCGUGAUUCCUGGCCUAUUAAUGAAUGGAGAAUAAACACUGGGUUGGCAGCAUGAGACAGCCCCGGGGCCCUUCCUGACAACCUUGCCUGUCUCUCUGUAAUGCUGAGAGCCUGUUUGCCAUCUCCUGGGUAUGUCUGAUAGGGUUGCUGCACUAUUUACUGUAUCUGCUCAUCAGGAGGACAAAAUCAUCUCAGUCUACCCAACAAACUGCCUUCAAGAUCAUUAUCUCUGAAGGCCCCCAUGGAGCCAUGUGCAACUCUGAAAGCAUUUCCAGGGAAUGGUGGGCUGGCUUCAUAAACGCUAAGUGAAAUUCUGUGUUUCUGCCAGACACAUUGAUAUAUAGAACAAUGCUGGUAAGGGUUCCCGCGUGGGAUUUUUUUUAACCCACCUGGGAGGUAUCCCCUGAACGGCAGUUGACAAUUAGCUGCUAAGUAAAAGGAGGCACUUAUUUUUAUUGCGGUCCUUGACAGCUUUAUGUUCACUGUUUAAAAGCUGGAGAGUCCUGUGUGUAAAGGUGAGUGGCGAGGGGAAGUGCUGGGGGAAGAAGGGCCGGGAGGGCUGGGGCAGGUGCAGACAGAUCCCAUGGUUUCCUUUUUGGAGUCAGAACCUGAGCAGUAUUUGCAAGCAUGUGCUGAUCUGGAAGUGAGAGAAGAGGGUUCUUCCAGUCUGGGGAGGAGGGAAGGCCUGAGGCUGGCUCAUCGGAGGCGUGAGUCUUCGGCCCUGCCAUGCCUCACAUCCCCAGGAUGCCGCGGUGGGAACUGGGCUGUGGCUUUCCUGCCCUGGCACUGCUUGUUUGCUGGGAUUUCAGGAGGAAAACCCCCAAGCUCCGAAAGAAAGCAGUGUUUGGCCAGCGCUUGGAUGAGACUGUGGCCUAUGAACAGAAAUUCGGCCCCCAUCUGGUGCCCAUCCUGGUGGAGAAAUGUGCAGAGUUCAUCCUGGAGCACGGCCGGAAUGAAGAGGGCAUCUUCCGUCUGCCUGGGCAGGACAACCUGGUGAAGCAGCUGAGAGACGCUUUUGAUGCUGGGGAGCGGCCCUCCUUUGACAGAGACACAGAUGUGCACACUGUGGCUUCCCUGUUAAAGCUCUACCUCCGAGACCUCCCAGAGCCCGUGGUUCCCUGGAGCCAGUACGAAGGGUUCCUGCUCUGUGGGCAGCUCACGAAUGCGGAUGAGGCAAAGGCUCAGCAGGAGUUGAUGAAGCAGCUCUCCAUCCUUCCUCGUGACAACUAUAGUCUCCUGAGCUACAUCUGCAGGUUCCUACAUGAAAUACAGCUGAACUGUGCUGUUAACAAGAUGAGUGUGGACAACCUGGCUACUGUGAUUGGUGUGAAUCUCAUCAGGUCGAAGGUCGAAGACCCUGCCGUGAUCAUGAGAGGGACUCCUCAGAUCCAAAGAGUGAUGACUAUGAUGAUCAGAGACCAUGAAGUCCUCUUCCCCAAGUCCAAGGAUAUACCCCUGUCACCCCCUGCCCAGAAAAAUGACCCCAAGAAAGCUCCAGUGGCCCGAAGCUCUGUAGGCUGGGAUGCCACUGAAGACCUCCGAAUUUCUAGGACAGACAGCUUCAGUAGCAUGACAAGCGACUCUGAUACAACCAGCCCCACCGGACAGCAGCCGAGCGAUGCGUUUCCGGAGGACAGCAGCAAAGUACCCAGGGAAAAGCCAGGAGACUGGAAAAUGCAAUCUCGUAAAAGGACUCAAACACUCCCUAACCGGAAAUGUUUCUUGACAUCAGCUUUUCAGGGUGCCAACAGCAGCAAAAUGGAGAUCUUUAAAAAUGAAUUCUGGUCGCCUUCCUCAGAGGCUAAGGCAGGGGAAGGGCACAGGAGAACGAUGUCUCAAGACUUGCGCCAACUUUCUGACUCCCAACGGACUUCCACCUACGAUAACGUCCCUUCCCUGCCAGGGUCCCCUGGGGAGGAAGCCAGUGCACUCUCUUCCCAAGCCUGUGACUCCAAGGGAGAUACUCUUGCCAGUCCAAACUCUGAAACUGGGCCUGGAAAAAAGAACUCUGGAGAAGAGGAAAUUGAUUCUUUGCAGAGGAUGGUCCAAGAGCUACGAAAGGAAAUAGAAACACAGAAGCAAAUGUAUGAGGAACAGAUUAAAAACCUUGAGAAGGAAAAUUAUGACGUUUGGGCUAAAGUGGUGAGGCUCAAUGAAGAACUGGAGAAGGAAAAGAAGAAGUCUGCAGCCCUAGAGAUCAGCCUCCGCAACAUGGAGCGCUCCCGGGAGGAUGUUGAGAAGAGGAACAAGGCCUUGGAAGAAGAAGUCAAGGAAUUUGUCAAAUCCAUGAAGGAACCCAAGACCGAGGCUUAAGGGUCCCAGGAGUACUGCAGGGACAGCCCCAGAGAGGCCCAACUCUGGCCCCUUUCUCAGUGCUAUCUGAUGACGGGGAAACAAAAUUAUUCUCUGAGAGGGAAAGGACAUUUGAGGGAAACAUCAAAUUUCCCCAUAAAUAAAUGAAUGGAGUUUGCAGGAAGGUGAGGGUGAGCAGAGAUGUGUGUGGACAUCUCUGACCAUCCAUCGCUGUAUUCAAAUGGAUUGUUUUAUUCCAUUCUGGUCUCAGGCAUGACCACGUCCAGUGAAGACAUUUGAGGCAGCACAUCUCAGGACCCAGGCAAUAGACUGGCCCCAACUCAGGCUGGACUAAGGUGUGAUUAAUUCUUUGUUUUUUGUGUGGAACAGCUCACCUUGUCAGACAGCCUCAGGGCAUCUCUGAGACACAGGGGCAGAAAAUGACAUUCAUCUUUUGAGUCCUCAUCCAUGGAGUGCUGUGUUUGGGGGGCUGCAUCUGCUGAAGCGAGAACCCCAUUCUGCCACCCCACCAGGAUGCCCAUUCUCCAGGACUUCUCCAACUUACUAUUAGACUAAACCAGAACAAGCAACAAACUGUAUUUAUGCAAGCAAAAUUGAUGAGAAAAUUAUAUUCAAAUAAAGCAAAAAUUAAAAAAAAAA